GGGAAUGGAGGCUGGACCCCUCUCCCCAAAGCCGAGGCUCGGUCCGCGCUCCUGCGACUAGGCUGAAGCUGCUCCCCUCUCCCCGCCGCCUCCGGGCGUUCCGGCCGUACACCCACACUGGGACUGGGACUGGGACUGGGCUGUGAUCCCGAGGCCGCAGCUCCGCUCUCGGCCCGCCACCUCCCCCGGGCCCACCUGCUCCCUCAGCCACAGGCCAUCUCGGGGCUCUGGGACUGGACGACUGCAGCCUCUUCCCUCUGCCCCCGGGAACGGCUCCACUCCGUCCCCUGCAGCGCCUGCAGCCGCGGCCCCCUCAGCAGCUGUGUCUCCUGGCGCCUCCUCGCCAUACCCAGCAGAGCAGUUGGAGCAGACAGCCAGGCUGCCCGGAGGAGUUUUUGGUGGGGUUUCUGCACUGAGGUGGAAACCCAGCAGAACCUGCCCUUCUUCCCUCCCCUGCUCCGCAAGGCAGCCCACCCCGACCUUGAGAUCCCAGGUUUGGAGAAUCCUGCUGAGAGCGAACAGUAGGAGGAUUCCCCAAAGCUUCCAGCUUGCCACCUGGAAGAAGGUCACUUUCUUUUGAGCAAAGGAGAUAACGGGAGGUACCCUGCCAAAGUUCACUGAGAGGCGGGGGUGACAUGGGCCACGGUUGCUCUGGGAGGGUUGUGGCACUCGGGGCUGGGUGGCUCUCCCUAAGCUUGCUCUGACAAAAGAGUUUUGAGUUGGUCUUUUGGCUGAGCCUGCCCAGGAAGGCAGGCUCCUGCAGGAGUCUUGGAGGGUCGGAUGCGGCGCCGGAUGAGGAUGAGGCGUGGCGGAAGAUGCGUUUGGCUCUGCAGACACUGCAUCGGGCAGCAGGGGACUCUGGGAGGCUGGUGCAGCCAGAAGGCAUGGCUCUUGACAGCCUUCUAGUAGAAUCUCUGGAAUUGUGCAUAUGAAGAAACAGAAACUCAGAGCAACUAAACAUUUGCCCAAAUGACUCCAACUGUAGGUGUCAGACAAAAGAAAAGAAAAGGACUUUUAGGUCCCCCCCGCCUCCAGCCAGCCUGUGCAGACUUGCUGCCUGCUGUGUCACCGGGAACGCAAAGGCUGGGAAGAAGGCCCUUCUCAAAAUGGACUGGUGUUGCAGGGUGAGAAGCUGCCCCCUGACUUCAUGCCAAAGCUCGUCAAGAAUCUCCUAGGCGAGAUGCCUCUGUGGGUCUGCCAGAGUUGCCGAAAGAGCAUGGAGGAAGAUGAAAGGCAGACAGGUCGAGAACAUGCAGUGGCGAUCUCCUUGUCACACACAUCCUGCAAAUCACAGUCUUGUGGAGAUGACUCUCAUUCGUCCUCGUCUUCCUCCUCAUCAUCCUCAUCCUCGUCCUCCUCUUCCUGCCCUGGGAACUCGGGAGACUGGGAUCCUAGCUCGUUCCUGUCGGCACAUAAGCUCUCGGGCCUCUGGAAUUCCCCACAUUCCAGUGGGGCCAUGCCAGGCAGCUCUCUUGGGAGUCCUCCUACCAUCCCCGGUGAGGCUUUCCCCGUCUCGGAGCACCACCAGCACUCAGACCUCACUGCUCCCCCUAACAGCCCCACCGGCCACCACCCGCAGCCAGCAUCUCUAAUCCCGUCUCACCCCAGCUCCUUUGGCUCCCCACCCCACCCACACCUGCUGCCCACCACCCCGGCAGCACCUUUCCCUGCCCAGGCUUCAGAGUGCCCUGUUGCUGCUGCCACUGCCCCCCACACUCCAGGGCCAUGUCAGAGCUCCCAUCUACCCUCCACCAGCAUGCCGCUCCUGAAGAUGCCCCCACCAUUCUCGGGGUGCAGCCACCCCUGCAGCGGGCACUGUGGUGGGCACUGCAGUGGGCCUCUCCUCCCACCCCCGAGCUCUCAGCCACUCCCUAGCACUCACAGGGAUCCCGGGUGCAAGGGGCACAAGUUUGCACACAGUGGCCUGGCUUGCCAGCUGCCCCAGCCCUGCGAGGCAGAUGAGGGGCUGGGUGAGGAAGAGGAUAGCAGCUCUGAGCGAAGCUCCUGCACCUCAUCCUCCACCCACCAGAGAGAUGGGAAGUUCUGUGACUGCUGCUACUGUGAGUUCUUCGGCCACAAUGCGGCAAAAGGAAAGGAAAUGGCAGAGAGAAAGCUAUGAUUCUGAUGAGUAUGUAUACGUGUGUAAUCCCAGAGAAGUGAACGCUUGGGAGUGAUGAAGGCAGAGUGGAAGCAAAAAGGCUCUCAGUCCCCCAAGUGUGACAGCCAGCCGAGGGACAGGCCGUGAGCACAGACGGCGCCAGGAAGGAGGCUCAGAUCAGAGGGCAUGCUGGCUCUGGCCAGGGGGAGGAAGCAGUGCAGAAGUCUCAUAAGCCACCCGCUGCCCCGACGAGUCGGAACUAUACCGAGAUCCGGGAGAAGCUCCGCUCGAGGCUGACCAGGCGGAAAGAGGAGCUGCCCAUGAAGGGGGGCACCCUGGGCGGGAUCCCUGGGGAGCCCGCCGUGGACCACCGAGAUGUGGAUGAGCUGCUGGAAUUCAUCAACAGCACGGAGCCCAAAGUCCCCAACAGCGCCAGGGCCGCCAAGCGGGCCCGGCACAAGCUGAAAAAGAAGGAAAAGGAGAAGGCCCAGUUGGCAGCAGAAGCUCUAAAGCAGGCAAAUCGUGUUUCUGGAAGCCGGGAGCCAAGGCCUGCCAGGGAGAGGCUCUUGGAGUGGCCCGACCGGGAACUGGAUCGGGUCAACAGCUUCCUGAGCAGCCGUCUGCAGGAGAUCAAAAACACUGUCAAAGACUCCAUCCGUGCCAGCUUCAGUGUGUGUGAGCUCAGCAUGGACAGCAAUGGCUUCUCUAAGGAGGGGGCUGCUGAGCCUGAGCCUCAGAGUCUACCCCCCUCAAACCUCAGUGGCUCCUCAGAGCAGCAGCCUGACAUCAACCUUGACCUGUCCCCUUUGACUUUGGGCUCCCCUCAGAACCACACGUUACAAGCUCCAGGCGAGCCAGCCCCACCAUGGGCAGAAAUGAGAGGCCCCCACCCACCAUGGACAGAGGUGAGGGGGCCCCCUCCCGGUAUCGUCCCCGAGAACGGGCUCGUGAGGAGACUCAACACCGUGCCCAACCUAUCCCGGGUGAUCUGGGUCAAGACACCCAAGCCGGGCUACCCCAGCUCCGAGGAGCCAAGCUCAAAGGAAGUUCCCAGUUGCAAGCAGGAGCUGCCUGAGCCUGUGUCCUCAGGUGGGAAGCCACAGAAGGGCAAGAGGCAGGGCAGUCAGGCCAAGAAGAGCGAGGCAAGCCCAGCCCCCCGGCCCCCAGCCAGCCUAGAGGUUCCCAGUGCCAAGGGCCAGGUCGCUGGCCCCAAGCAGCCAGGCAGGGUCCUAGAGCUUCCCAAAGUAGGCAGCUGUGCUGAGGCUGGAGAGGGGAGCCGGGGGAGCCGGCCAGGACCAGGUUGGGCUGGCAGUCCCAAAACUGAGAAGGAGAAGGGCAGCUCCUGGCGAAACUGGCCAGGCGAGGCCAAGGCACGGCCUCAGGAGCAGGAGUCUGUGCAGCCCUCAGGCCCAGCAAGGCCACAGAGCUUGCCCCAGGGCAAGGGCCGCAGCCGCCGGAGCCGCAACAAGCAGGAGAAGCCAGCCUCCUCCUUGGACGAUGUGUUCCUGCCCAAGGACAUGGACGGGGUGGAGAUGGAUGAGACUGACCGAGAGGUGGAGUACUUUAAGAGGUUCUGUUUGGAUUCUGCAAAGCAGACUCGUCAGAAAGUUGCUGUGAACUGGACCAACUUCAGCCUCAAGAAAACCACUCCUAGCACAGCUCAGUGAGGCCCUGCCCAGGCUGAGCUGCUUCAGGGCGUCCUGAGGCCCUGACUGCCAGCUGAAGGCGUAUAAUUUUUCCCUCCGUGUGCCCCACCUACCCGUCCAAGACCCUCUGUGCUCCCCACCAUCCUGGACCAACCAAAAGCUGAACGGAUGCCACACUGUGCUGGGGCCCCUUGACCUCAGCAGAGCCGCUUCCUGGUGCUACGCAGCCUCCACACUCAGAGCCCGUGGACUGGGCUGGCCUAAGGGCCAGGGCUGAUGGUACUGCUGGCCCAACACUGCUCUCUUUGUGUUUGGUUUUUUUGUUUUUGUUUUUAUUUUGUUUUUUUCCAAUUCUUUACUUUUGAUACUGUGAAGAUCUUUCGUGCCGAAAGAUAAAGCAACAUUUGGACACAGAG